GUGUAUGUGUGAAAAUCAGGAAGAGCCAGCGGGGAGUGUGUGUUGCCAUCGCGUCUCCGCCUGCAGGUGCAGACAUCUGGAGGAGAGAGUCGGAGAGCAGAAACCACUUGGCUCCCAGACAAUUCCCCUACAGGCUUUGGGCCUGGAAUUGAGGAGAAAGUGAGCUAAGUUGGGGUGGGGUGAGUCCAAAGAAGCACGGGCUGGGCCAAGCUAAGCUGCUCUGGGCUGGGCUGAUCCCUCCCCACUCAGGGGCGGGACCCCAGGAGGAGGGAGAGGACAGAGCCACUGCAGAGGACCAGACUGGGAAAACAACGAUAUGGCAGGAGCCAGUCUUGGGGCCCGCUUCUACCGGCAGAUCAAAAGACAUCCGGGGAUCAUCCCGAUGAUCGGCUUAAUCUGCCUGGGCAUGGGCAGCGCUGCGCUUUACUUGCUGCGACUCGCCCUUCGCAGCCCCGACGUCUGCUGGGACAGAAAGAACAACCCGGAGCCCUGGAACCGCCUGAGCCCCAAUGACCAAUACAAGUUCCUUGCAGUUUCCACUGACUAUAAGAAGCUGAAGAAGGACCGGCCAGACUUCUAAGCCAGGCUGGGCUGCCAGUGCCAUGCAAGCCACAGCCAGCCAGCCCAUCCACUUCUUCCACUCCUCCCCGCAGGCCCCAAGGCAUCACUCCGGCCACCCUGUCCCGCUACUGCUUACACAGGCCGGGUUCCCACGCAGAGGGGAGGCUGCUCCACCCCUACUCUCCUCCCUUGCUCCCAGCAGCGGAAGCGCCUCUGACCCUUGGCUUGAGUCCCACGUGGGGGAGGAGGAGGCAGGCAGCACCAGCAGGGGUCCACCAAGAGCCCAGACCAGCCCCUCUGCCCUCCUACCCGGGCCUCGAAGGGUGUGGCACAGGCUACGUGUUGAGCGUGGCCUACGUGAGCCAACAAGAAGCAGGGGCCUCUGAGUGCCAAGCGACGUGGCGGGCUCCACGUUAGCCCAGGCUCUGAGAGCCAGCCCAGGGGCGGCGCUGCUCAGCUUGGGCUGGUCCAGGGCCUGCCCAGGCUGGGGCACCUUUGCCUCCUGAGGCGCAGCGCACUCCUCCCCUGCCCAAGCCUACUGCCUCCCGCUGCCGCCAGUACCCCCUCCAGCCCCACACCUGGGCCUCCCCCUGCCACUCCCCUCCCUUGCUCCCCUCUGUCCCCAGGGAUCAAACAGAAGCAGCCGUGGGCAAAAUACAAUUUCAUUUAACAAAUUGAA